GGUGUUACUGUGUUGCCCAGGCUGGUCUUGAAAUCCUGGGUUGAAACAAUUCUCCUACCUUGGCCUCUCAAAAUGCUGGGAUUACAGGCGUGAGCCAUCAUGGCUGCUGCAAAUACUUAUUGCAUGAAGAAUAGAUUUAAGAUAAAAUAGACUUCCCAGAGAACAGCUUCCGCUGCACUACACUGAAUACAUACACGCAUACCAAGGAAAAACAGCACUGGAGGCAAUGUUUCUAUAAAUCAAAGAAGAGACAGUGUGAGAAUGUCAGCCCUCAACUGGAAGCCGUUUGUGUACGGGGGGCUGGCCUCCAUCACUGCUGAGUGCGGUACAUUUCCAAUUGAUUUAACCAAGACACGGCUCCAGAUUCAAGGCCAGACGAAUGAUGCAAAAUUUAAGGAAAUUAGAUACCGAGGAAUGUUGCACGCAUUAGUGAGGAUAGGCAGAGAAGAAGGGCUGAAAGCACUCUACUCGGGGAUUGCCCCCGCGAUGUUACGCCAGGCAUCCUAUGGCACCAUCAAGAUAGGCACUUACCAGAGCUUGAAGCGACUAUUCAUUGAACGCCCAGAAGAUGAAACUCUACCGAUAAAUGUGAUAUGUGGAAUUCUGUCUGGAGUCAUAUCUUCAACCAUUGCUAAUCCAACUGAUGUUUUGAAAAUUCGGAUGCAAGCGCAAAGCAACACCAUUCAAGGAGGAAUGAUAGGCAACUUCAUGAACAUUUACCAGCAAGAGGGGACAAGAGGACUGUGGAAGGGUGUGUCCCUUACUGCGCAGAGGGCUGCUAUUGUUGUUGGUGUGGAGCUGCCGGUCUAUGACAUCACCAAGAAGCAUCUUAUUCUCUCAGGCCUGAUGGGAGACACUGUGUAUACCCACUUCCUCUCAAGCUUCACCUGUGGUCUGGCAGGGGCCCUGGCCUCAAACCCUGUUGAUGUUGUGAGGACACGUAUGAUGAAUCAGAGAGUGCUUCGAGAUGGCAGAUGUUCUGGCUACACAGGAACCCUGGAUUGCUUGUUACAGCUUACAGUGCUGGAAAGUUUUUCCACCACAGCAAAGCCACAAAAGCUUAUCAGCGUAGAUGCCAUCUCAGAAGAGGCUGAUACCAGGGGAUUUACAUAUCUCAGCUGUGAUCUUUCUGCUCCAAGCUGACCUUGGAAGAUAGUUUGAUGUGGUUAAGGGUGGAACCCCUUUUAUUUAAUCGUGUCCAUAGCGUGGGUCUGCCUGUACCUAUUUGUUAUUAAGUGUGCCAUUUGUAAGUCUGUUGUUAUGCACUGGAGUUGUGAAGAUGGCAUUUUCUGUGUCAUCCUUAACCCAUAACCACAGUUCUUUGUGACAUACGAGCAGUUGAAGAAAUUGGAUUUGUGACAAGCCAAGGCUGCAUGAGACAUCUUUCUGAAAAUGGUAACUUCUGAAACAGCAAAGCUUCCUGUGUUUCACUCUGCUUCUCACUGCUUGGCUCAUCACAGAUUCUGGGAUGUGAGCAACAGAUGAAGACUGGGUUAGUUGAGAUUGCUGUGUGUUGGCAUUGGAUGCUCUUCAUCAAACGUUUAAUGGCAUAAACUAACAUCCAAACACUAGUCUUUACCACUGAAGUGCCCUUCAACAUCAAAGAUAAUAUGUGAAAUGCAUGUUUCUUGCUAAAGAAAACUUGCAAGAAAAUCAGGAGCGAUGUAUUGUUUUAUUCAGGGAGAGUAGCUCCUGAUGCAUCUCAGCUCAUGACUGAGAAUCAGACUGCUCUAGAAAAGCUCACUGGAACCAUGGAAUGGAGCCUCCGAGAAGGUGUUAUGGUUUCUGAAUUUCUGGGAGAUUUUGCUCCUUGUCAACUGAAGAAAUUUCAUGUAUGGAGACCUGGACUGUUCAACCCCAGGUAUAAACGGUGCAGGAAAUGGAUCCUAGGAAUAUCACACUGCUUUAUCAUUUCCUAUUUUGGCAGGAUCUUCCACUUAUAAUAAGUGAUUUUAAGCUUUGAAGACUUGACAUUUGUGAGAAAUUGUUACAAAGUAAUAAUCUCUAAAUUCGUGGUGGUGUUAUGUGUUGGCUUUGAAGGUUGCAAGGUCUGUAUUGGUGGGGGGUGUUUUCAAGCAGCUUAGGUUCUGUCUUAGGUCAUGUUAGUAAUUAGCUUUAUGAUUUUUAGCAAAGCAUAUGUAUUUCUCAAUGAGUAAAAUGGGGAUAAUAACGUCUAUUGAUGUAGAGGGUCAAAUGAAGAACAAAUAGUAGCUGCUGCUACUUGACUGGAAAGGUAAAUGUGUUUACAUCAUGCUGUGGAACAGCUCUAAACAGUCUAUGUAGAAGAGGGGCAUGUUCUCAUGGGCUUCUCAUGGUAAUUGUGAAUGAAGCCCUUUGUUAAGGUCUUGUUGAAGAAAGAACACUGUAUAAGUUCAGGCUUUAGUACAUUUUCCUUAGCAAAAUGUUGGUAGUGAAUCAAAGAGUUGAUUUUUCCAGGUUUCCAGUUUUUACUUUAGUUUAUGUUGUGCCUGUCUUGGACUUUCUGUUUAGUUUGGAUGGAAAAUACCUGCUUGAAAUUUUAAAAAUGAUUUCUUUAGUGCAUCUAUUUAGCUAGUUUCUGAUAGGUGGUAUGUAAUAUUUUCCCUUUUUCUUUCCUUCUGUAGACACAAUAAGUCAUUCUCCCUCUUCUUUUUUUCUUUUUCUAUUUUCUUAUUCUUUACUCUAACCUGCUUCAGAGAAAGAGCCCUCUUCCUUCUUGUCUUCAUCUUAGUCUUUUCAAAAUAAAAGAUGACUGUGAGAACCCCAAGAACUUCCACUUCUGGGAGGCAGCCACAGGACAGGGAACAUAUUUAUUUGGGUCUCUUCAGUUCCCCCUUUGAGAACAACAUUAAAUACAUGUUAGCUGGGGCUCCAGGGCAUUCUCCUUCCACAGUAGUGCGGCCAAAUUCCCAGUCUGGCCAGUCUCUUUGUUGAGACUGAAUAGAAGGACUGCAGGUUUUUUUGGAGGAUGAGAUAAUUUUUCCUCGCAGGCAUUUUUCCCUUGCCUUCCUUAUGCAUGAAUGGUCCCUUUGAAUAUUAUUUCCAAAAGUGAGAGCUAAGACAAAGUCAUCAAAAAGAGAGGAUAACAGAAGGUGGGGGCGGGGGCGGGGUGCAGUGGGGUAGGGUUACCUGUUAAUUGCUGAGACUCAGAUGAAAGUCCAGCUCUCCCUGGGCAACCCUAGAGGGCAGCAGAGGACCCCAGAGCUCAUUCAGGCCUUGCUGCUUGUUCUAAACUACACCUUAGGAUUUUUUCUUCUUUCCAAAACAUUCCAUUGAUUUUAUAAAGACUUUCUAUAGAGAGGCUUUCACUUUUGAGUUCUUUGAGUUUAAAGAUUGCUUUUCUUGAAAUGCUCUUUUUUUAAUGUAGAAAAAUUUUACUUUUUCAAAUAUGCAUACAAUUUUUAAAACAGUAGAAGCAAAUUCAUUUUAAUGACCAUGUAAAGAGCGAAUGUCAGACAGUAUUAUUACCAGUUUAUUCAAAUUACAUACAUGUUCCUACCAAGGUGGAAAGAAAUUCAAACCUCAUGGUAAAACUUAAGCACGAUUUAAGAUAAAAGCAUAGUAUUUCUUCAGUGUAGACUUAUUAAGUGCCUUAUUGAACAGGAUCUUAACCUGCUUUUUCUGUUUUUUUGAAAGAGUUAAUGCAAUUGUUGAAGCUUCUAACCAAGAAACAACUUAAGGAAUUGGGAGACUUGGUCCCCUCGUUGUCAGGGUUCUGGCUAUAAGUACCUCCCCACCUUUGGGUUUUCUUAAAUAUGCCAAAAGGAAUUCUAGUUUUUAUAACCAAUGGGUUUUUUUGUUUGUGUGCUUAUGGAUUUGUGUAAUCAUUGAUGCUUAAUGUUGUGGAUUCAUAAUAUAAAAAGUGGCUCCUGUCCUUUAUAUUUAUUCAUGUGCUAGAAAUAGUAUGCAUUAUAUAAAGAGUAUGAAGUUUUCAUAAGCCUUUAUAUUUCAAGCUCUUUAUUUAAACAUUGUUGGAAUAUGUGGCAUAAGCCUUGUUUCAUUUAUUUAAUAAACUGGAGUAAUAUAUAAUAAUAAAAA